AGAAUUCAGCUGAGAGACAGAGGUCAGACAUGCCAGCAGGGUUGGAAAGAGGCAGGUACGGAAGCUGAGCUGCAGAGUUAGCCGGCAUCUGACAGAAAAAUGUGAGUGUGCUGUGGAAGGCUUGCAUUUCCUUUAAGGUAGACCUCUUUGAAAGUAGAAUUUUCACGGAAUUGUUUUCUUUCUCACUGAGUGACUGAUUUAACAGAACUCUCACCUUCUAUGCAAGCGCACCUAGUUUUAGAGCUCCGUGACGGCAAUGUUCAAUUAGUUCAUUAUUAACUGAGCAAUGCAGAAUGCUUUAUCCAGGGUGCUUGGAGAAGAUGUCAGAGUUUGUCUACAGAUUUUGAGCGUUCGAAGUUGACCCCUGACUAAGUAUACUUUGCUGCUCCCUCAGCCUUUGAAAAAAUGUCUGUCACAUAUGAUGAUUCCGUUGGAGUAGAAGUGUCCAGCGACAGCUUCUGGGAGGUCGGGAACUACAAGCGGACUGUGAAGCGGAUCGACGAUGGCCACCGCCUGUGCAGCGACCUCAUGAACUGCCUGCAUGAGCGGGCGCGCAUCGAGAAGGCGUAUGCGCAGCAGCUCACUGAGUGGGCCCGGCGCUGGAGGCAGCUCGUGGAGAAAGGGCCCCAGUACGGGACCGUGGAGAAGGCCUGGAUGGCCUUCAUGUCCGAGGCAGAGAGGGUGAGCGAGCUGCACCUCGAGGUGAAGGCCUCACUGAUGAACGAUGACUUCGAGAAGAUCAAGAACUGGCAGAAGGAAGCCUUUCACAAGCAGAUGAUGGGCGGCUUCAAGGAGACCAAGGAAGCUGAGGACGGCUUUCGGAAGGCACAGAAGCCCUGGGCCAAGAAGCUGAAAGAGGUAGAAGCAGCAAAGAAAGCCCACCAUGCAGCGUGCAAAGAGGAGAAGCUGGCUAUCUCACGAGAAGCCAACAGCAAGGCAGACCCAUCCCUCAACCCUGAACAGCUCAAGAAAUUGCAAGACAAAAUAGAAAAGUGCAAGCAAGAUGUUCUUAAGACCAAAGAGAAGUAUGAGAAGUCCCUGAAGGAACUCGACCAGGGCACACCCCAGUACAUGGAGAACAUGGAGCAGGUGUUUGAGCAGUGCCAGCAGUUCGAGGAGAAACGCCUUCGCUUCUUCCGGGAGGUUCUGCUGGAGGUUCAGAAGCACCUAGACCUGUCCAAUGUGGCUGGCUACAAAGCCAUUUACCAUGACCUGGAGCAGAGCAUCAGAGCAGCUGAUGCAGUGGAGGACCUGAGGUGGUUCCGAGCCAAUCACGGGCCGGGCAUGGCCAUGAACUGGCCGCAGUUUGAGGAUGAAGAGUGGUCCGCAGACCUGAAUCGAACCCUCAGCCGGAGAGAGAAGAAGAAGGCCACUGACGGCGUCACCCUGACGGGCAUCAACCAGACAGGCGACCAGUCUCUGCCGAGUAAGCCCAGCAGUGUGAGCAGCUACGAGAAGACCCAGAGCUAUCCCACCGACUGGUCAGACGAUGAGUCUAACAACCCCUUCUCCUCCACGGAUGCCAAUGGGGACUCGAAUCCAUUCGACGACGACGCCACCUCGGGGACGGAAGUGCGAGUCCGGGCCCUGUAUGACUAUGAGGGGCAGGAGCAUGAUGAGCUGAGCUUCAAGGCUGGGGAUGAGCUGACCAAGAUGGAGGACGAGGAUGAGCAGGGCUGGUGCAAGGGACGCUUGGACAACGGGCAAGUUGGCCUAUACCCGGCAAAUUAUGUGGAGGCGAUCCAGUGAUGAGUCGGGGACAGGCCAGCGGGGGGACGGAGGCGGCGGGCCCAGGAGCCUCAGCCAGCCACGUGGGCAUCCACUCCUUUUCCUGCAAGAGAUGAUGGUUCCAUUGCUCUUGGCUUCAUGGUGUUCCUGGAAGGCAGAUGAGCUGGUCAUUUCGCCUGGGACUCGGCACCUUUCCGAGUGCAGCUGGAGGGAUCUGAGCGCAGGAAGACGCAGAACAACAGAAAUAGCCGCCCCUCCCCGCCCACUGUGCCUGUUGGCCUAUCAUAGAUCUCUAUGUUCUUGACUUUGUCUCUCCUUUCCGAGUCAAUGGUGGGUUACACUGAUCUUGUUCCACUGAUUACUCUCUCUGACGAGUCCAUCACCUGCAACUUAAAUGAACAAGCUUACAUCCCAUUUUGAGUGAAGAUUUUGAGGUUUUUAAUUUAAAGGCUGUGUACAGUUAUACUUUUUUAUACACCUGUUCAUUUCUACUUAAAUUAUGGCACAGAUUGAUGCGCACCAGUCUUGAGGAAACGAUCUCCCUAUUCCCUUACCCUGUUACUCAGCCACGCCGUGUGUAGGCUUAGCCUCAGGUGGCAGAUGUUUGAGGAAAGGAAUUAUGCCAGGAAGGUGGGACCGGGUUAUGGUCGGGUUUCUAUUGGGAAUGCUCUUUGUGCUUUUGGGCAUCUGAAUGGAAGCUUUACAUAGAACCUUAGGUAGAACUCCCCCAAAUCGCCAUAUUUAAAAAUUAUUUUCACUCUAUUCUUGCUUAAAACUGUACUCUUUUGCAAAUUAACAAUUUUAUCACUGAUUCAGAGUUAAAAAGAAGACUAACUUUUCAAGCAAAUGCAUCUGUAAAGAUGCUUUAGAUUAGACUGUCAUGUCUCAGUGUCUAUCUGUAUAUAUUAUUUGAUAUUCAGAGAAUCUAAAGCACUCGUCUACUGUUUUAAUGAGAUUUAACAGCUUUUAACAGUGAGUUUCGUUUGUAAACUGCUUGAAGUCUGUGGCAUUCAGGCACACGUCUGGCUGGCCGGCUGGGUCUCCUCCCGGGCUCAGUGGGCCUGGGGCCUCUCUGACGUGGUGCCUGCUGGAGGGAGGCUCGUCGUCACCAGCUGACUGCUGGUCCGGCUUCUGACCGGCCUUUGUCCUGGCUCCGUAGCAGAACACUGUAAAAGUGCCCGCGUCUUUGCAGUAGUUGCAGAUUUCAGUCGUCGUGUUACUUGUGCACAAACAGAAGCUGGGUCUUACCCGCAGCACGAGUGUCUCGGGCUGCCCGGAGUCGCCCGGGAGCAGGUGCUGCAGCCAGAGUUACGCGGGGGCCACGCGGGCCGGCGGGGGUGGGGGGAACGUGGGGGAACCUGUGUUUCACGUGACUCAGCAGUGCCCGCCGCCGUCACCAGCUAUGCAUUCACUCCGUUUCCAGUGAGCAGAUGUCUUGCUUGGAAAGUGGACCUGUGUCUGUGUCUGUCCUGAGAACUUACCAGCAGAAAUCCUCAUUUCUGUGCUACGGAUUUACCAAAAAUUGUCAAGUCUUUUUCAGUUUAACAGUUCCUUUACAUGUGUAGUAUUUGAGGAAAAAAAUCAAUAAACAGUUGAUCUCGUGCAUAUGGAA